UUAAGUGGAAAUAUAUCAAGUAAACAGACAGUUAUGUAUUUAAAUAACCAUCAUAAUCCCCAGGAAGUAGACAGCACCUCUGCCUUGGGCAGCGGUUUGCGGGCACACAAGUCUCGAACUGAAAUAAGCAGGCAAGACAUAAUUAGACAGCGCUUCUCAGCCUACAGUGGUGCCUUACGAGUCUGAGCGACCAGGUCUGCGCAUGGAGAGCCCGGCCUUCUUAGGCGGCGACAGGUGUGUCCUCCGGACGGGCUCCUGGCCGUCUCCACCAGCUUUCUCGGGCUGAACGCGGCUGGGCUCCCCCAAGGCCUCCCCUUGCUGACGGCUCCACGCCUGCUGGACGAGAAGCGGCCUCCCCGGGGCGUCGCAAGCCCCUGGGACAAGAAGAGGAGCCGACAUUGAGGGAGACCUGAGCAGUGGACGCAGGCAGCGUCAGCCUGGGCGUCCCCGGAGUCGCGGCGAGACCCUGGCUCCCCACCACCGCCCGGCUCUCAGCUUUGGCAUCGCGUCUCCAGAGAGGGCGGUGGAUGACGAGGAACUGCAGCAGUGUACGACCCCCGGGCUCCAGACGACCCUGGGGAGAGCGCGCAGAGUUCCUGGCUAGCGGCCCCCUCGCAGCCGGGCACCCCUUCUCGGCUGCGCGCAGCCACUUAGGGGCACAAGAUAAGCCCCUGGGGAGGGAGCGGGCUGCAGGCGCGGUGGGGAAGAACGGCCCGGACGCAGCCGGGCACAGGGAAGGCCGGGCCUGCAGACUGGAGAGACGUGGGCUGCGGUGAAACCGUUAGGGCUGCUUUGCCGCGCACAGACGCGGAGGCCUUUACAAGGCCGGCAGGCCUCGCCCAGGGCCUGGGCCGCCGCAGGUGCCUUUGGGUCACACCCGGGGCGAAUCCCACCCCCUCCUGGGGCCGCUUCUGUUUACCAAACCCCUCAGGCUAUUGCGUUAGUUGUGCGGGGGAAGGAUAGAGGCAGGGUCCUCUGGUGGAGGGGAGGGAACUGGGGACCCGGGGCUGCUGGGGACGCAGGCGACAGAAUGAAAGGCGAAGAGGCGGCAGCUCGAAUCUGUCUGGGGGUGAUUUUAACCGGCGCAGAGGUGCAGCAUAUGCUUUCCAGGUUGGACUGCGGAAUACAAAGAACGACUCUGAGCCCGGGGAGCCUCCUGACACCGAAACCAAACGAUCCCGACCUAGGGGGGCUGAGUGGCAGGAGACUGGAUUUUUUGUUGAGUUGCAAUUAAAGGGAGAUAAUUAAGCCCGGAGCCGCGCAGCUUAUUAAUAUUUAUAGCCCGGAGCGACAGGGCCUGCGCUCGCUGGAAGCGGAUUUGCAGGCCCAGGCGCGGAGCCGGUGUCUCCUGAGCCAGGGGCUUCGCAGACUCGGGAGGAGAAGGCUCGAUGGGGAAAUUGGGGAGCGUCCGCCUUCUGCGUUUCUCCUAAUUACGCCAGCGGUCAAAGUCCGGCCGGGCCGGAACGUCCCGAAGGCCGGGAACCGCGCGAUGCCCGAAUGCGGGGCGACCCGGCCGCAGUAUCCAGCAUUUCGGAAGCCCAGUUAGGUCUCGUCUCUUUGUUAAUUACCCAAACUGCAUCUCGCAGUAUGUUUCUGCCCACGGGGACAGACCGCGCGUUAAGGAAAUGGCCCAAUAAUUAGGACUCGGGGUAGAAUGUGUCUUAUUUUCUUGGAGCAUGUGGGGCAAAGGAGACAGUAGGUACAUGCGGCCCUGGCUUUGGGGCAAUUUUGCAAAAAAGAAAACGCCCUCCGGCCUCGAAUUUCGUCCGCGGUCGGCCAGGCGCCGCGCUUUGGUUCCUUUCCCACUCCGCGGUCCCCGGGUGUGGGCCAAAGCCCGGACCGGCGGGAGGGGCUCCCGGUGCCCGCGUCGCUGGCCCGGCCUGGGGGAUGCGCCCGAGCGGGCUGGAAGGAGGGGCUGCACAGGCGGCGCCCACAGGGUCGUAGCGCCCGGGCUGGGAGCCUGAGAGCGGUAGGUUCCCGGCCUGCGGCCGCGCGCUCAACUCCCGGAAAAUGCGCGCGAAGCUUUUGCCGUUUGUACCGCACGCGGUUCUCGGAUCUCUGCUUUUCGCGCACGGCCGGUGGGGGCGGGGAGGAAGCGCGGGUGGGAGUGGGCGGCCGCGGUUAGCUUCUCCUGUCCGAACGCAGGGUUUCACUGGGGCGCCGCUACGGUUCCUAUGGCAACGCGGCUCCUCGACGCAGCCCAGGAGUCGCGGUCGCGGGAGGCUGCGCCGCGCACCGAGCUCUUCCCUGUGGCCGCCGCAGCCGCCAGCCUCUUCCUGCUCAUGCUUUUCCUCAUCUUCAUCUCGGUCUGAGUGGGCUCUGGACCUCUCCACCAGCCUCUGCCCCAGAACUGUUAACUGCGGGGGGGAAAAAAGGAAUUUGUCGUCGCAACGCGCGUUCCGAUGGAGCCGCACGCCACAAAGGAAGACUCAUGCUGCACCCCGCGGGGCAGAUGCGGCGACACUGGACAUCGCUGCACAGCUGGGUCUGCCCGUUUCCAGAGCUGCUUAGCGCCGACGCCCAUAAAUGAGGAGGACUCCCUGUGUAUUAAAAGGGGGAUCCGCAGGGUUUAAUUUGAUAAGGAUUAUAGCCUUCAUAAAGGCAUUUUUAACAAAAAGAUGUAGGUGGCAUGGUAAUCGAGUAUUAUUUACGCAUCUCUCCGCACACGCACUCAUACCUGAAAACGUUUUGGCAGGCACAAAAUGAUUUUUUUGUGUAUAAAGAAUGUGUGUAACUCGUGGAUGGUGGGGUUCAGCAGGACAGAUUAGUGACAUUAGAUAAUUUACAACGAGGAUUAUGUUUGUGCUGAAAAUAAAAGCUAUAUUGUUUAUUUAGUUCAUUGCCA